ACUCUUAGAACAACAGCCACUUUUGUGGGAGCCCAAGAAACAGCAGCUUUAAAACAGGGUAAAUAUUCAGGCAUCAUUAGGAUCCUGAAUACAAGCCAGCCAGUAAAAUACGGGAUCUACUCAGAAGGGCACAAUCUAUCAGAUGGUCAAGACAAAUAAACCUGGGGCCAAGGUAGCGGUUUCAGCACAGAGAGGGUCUGAGGUUACUACUAACACAUCCCCUCAGCAGGGACAUGGGUACGUUCUUGCCUCAAGCCAUCGAAGUGCUGCAGUCUCCCUGAACCCUUCCCACCGAAGAUCAGAAGCUGCACAUCCCACCACUCCCCAUUCAGCAUCAGACUACCCUCGAUCUGUCUCCCUCCAGUCAGGACCUGGACACUAUGCAGUACCCACUCCUCGGGGACCCGAGACUGGACCAAGAACAGAAUCAUCCCGCCAUUCCUCUCCCCAUCUAAAGAGCCAGAAGACUCAGACACUGGCUUCCCAUGCUUCAAGCAGACAAUGGAAAGUUAGUCCACCCAGAGAGGAAGCAGCACGAAGAGGCAGUGAGAGCAAGUCAGGGCGCGAGGUCGGCCAUCAUGCUUCAUCAAUCCCAGAUGCCAAAUCUACUCAUCAGUUGAGUUUUCAAGACCAGAAGAAUAACUUACAAUCACAAAUCUUAGAAGAUGACCCACCAUCCAAGGUCCAGAACCCCCAAGGAGUCAGAGUUCCCCGUAGGAUUUUGUCUUACCCAAAGGAUGAAGCAGUACAAACUGAGCCCAUCCAAAGAAUUACGACUACUAGUGAGAUCAGAUCUCCAAGGAGUCCCUCUCUCCUAGAGCACGGAAGCAGCUGUGUCUCUGCAGACUAUCAGACAGCCCAGAGAAGGGUCCCUGUAGAAGAAUCAGAAACAGGUCCUUACGGUCCAAUUCCUUCAAAACCCAAGGCCUUGUAUAGGAAUAUGAACUUGGACUCAUUGCUCAAACUCUCUGUCCUUAAAGAUUCUGAUGGUGUACACCGAGUUUCUGCACGGGUAGACCCUGAGUCUCUUCAUAAGUAUUCUGCCUAUCCUGAAACCAAGCCCUCCGCAAAGGUCUUAGUAUCAUCACAGGUGGAGUCCAACGUGAGGACCCCAAUCCGAGGAAACAGCGAGGUUGGCCGCAGGGUCACCAUCUCCCCAGGGGUACAGUCAGUAGAGCCAACUCACCAUGUGACAGUUCCAUCAGUGUCUGAGGGCUCCCACAAGUCAUCCAUGUUUGUUACUCCAGAGCCCAUCUAUAAACAGCAAACCCAAAAACCCCCAGAAAUUACUUACAUGUCCCAAGGACCUACACCCAGGUAUCCAGAACUCUCGCAAAAGCCCUCCAUCCAUGCAGAACUGGAACUGACCCCUAGGCCCUUGCCUCCUCGGUCCUUACCUAGGUACGGACCUGACUCCUCAUGGUGGCCCUUGCUGAAUCCUGAAGUUGAAACACCCCAAAGCCAGCUGACAACACCGGAUUUUGAGCCUAAGUGCUCUCCUUCCCUAGAUCUUUUAUUGUCCGGUUUUAAAAUAGACUCUAGCCCUUUCUGUGAGGAUCUGAAGUUCCAGAGAGAGAAGGCAAGCCUAUCACCACCAUCACCACCAAAGGAGUUUCCAAGUUGGGCACCACUGAGUGAAGUGCCACAGACCCCCAAGCACACCUGCAAACAACCCAUUCAAAGGUUUACUGCUUUCUUCCUGGAUGUCUCUGAGGAAAUGUACAAUCGUGUCAUCUGGUGGCUAAAAGAUGAGGAGCUACCAUGGGCAGCCAAUUCCAGAGCAGGAUGGAAGGCUGGUGGCCUCUGGCUAAGACUUGCUAACCUGGGGACAGGAUGAAGAAAUUGAGGCUCAGAGUUUGUUCAUCAAAGCUGGAAGCAUUUUAAGGAGCAGUCUGUCCCAGGGAGUCAACUAUAUGGUAUAGAAACCCUUCUUCUAUAGCCACGUCUCCCUGGAAAAUACUUCUCAAUAUUUCAGCAGCACCUUUAGAUAUCAAGAAUUGUGAAGGGAAAGGUUUUAGUGAGAGUAACAUCUGUGUCUUUGUAUGUGAACCACGGGGCUGGGAGGUGGGUGUGAGCUUGUGAGCAGCCAGGAUGAAGGGCAAGUGAAGGGUCAAUGAAGCGCAGAGCCUCAAGGCUUGUCUGGGCUCUAAAAUCAGAAUGGAAAACUAAUCAAUGAGUCCUUUUAGUCAAUCCAUAUUGAUCAGCCAUCUCCUGGGGGCAGAGGCCUGGACACCCAGAAAAACAUCACAUCACAUGUUUGCUGAUUUGAAGUGAGCAGAGGUUAAAAGAAAAGACAUAGUCCCUGCCCUUGAGGAGCUUGUGGUGAAUUUGGUAGAGAAAAGUAUACAGAUGGGUCACUUGAAAGGGUGUGGACAUCAAAGGACAAAGCAAAGUCCAAUGAAAUGAGUCAGCAAAGCUUCCAGCAUGGAGGCAUAUGGAGGGUAAAAGCCAGGGAAAGACAGAUUUUGGCUCAGUAUAGUGAAGACUUUGGUAACUUGGCAGCCCAAAGGUUGAAGGGCAGUUGUUAGAAUCAGUGAAUUUUUGGCCAUCGGAGGUAUGUAUUCGAGCAGAGGCUGGGAAGGCAGGGGAGCCUUCAGACAUCUGGUGAGUAGUCACAUUAGGAGGUUUGUAAGUCCUUUCCAACCCUGAGCUCCUAUGGCCCUGCCCUGUUCACGGAGGGUGUUGGAAGGACUGUCUGCCCUAUCAGAGUGGCUGGCUUCUAGCACCCUGCCAGCUCUGGAACUGCCCCUCUUUGCAGCCAUUCAGCAGGUGCCAGGAAACACAGUGUUCCCCAGCCUUGCCACCCACACCUUAUGCCUGCCCCCAGGAUCAUGGGACACAUGGCAGCAGCUGGGGGAAGAUUUGGGCUUAAUGUAUUUUGGUUUAUUGCCUUUGUCCACCACAGACCUUGUUGGACAGACUUGCUGAGGUUUCCUUGAAAGACACAACCCAGUGAUAGCCUUUGGUCCAAGGACUCUCUGACUGUAUCGUCAGUGACUCAUCUAUCUCACUGGGGAAGGGAUGUACAAUUAGUUCUUGCGCCACUUUAGGGAAACUUAGCUACUGAAAGGCAGAAGUGGCCAUUGCUAGUCAUGCAGAUCUGAAAUCCUGAUUUCCUGUGGUAAUUGCUCUUUAUUAUCGGCUUUGAACCUGGGCCCUGGGAUGGCCCACAUGCAGCCUCCUUGCUUAGGUCCUGUGCCAUACAACCUGCACCUAUGGGUGGGCAGGAAAGACCUAGUGGAGGGGGCCAGGACAUAUCAUGUUGGCCUGACCUAAGCAACGGAGCCCAAGACAGCAGGCUAGAGCUAUGGUGGCUGAGCUGAGUUUCCCAGCUAGACACUCCCCUAGACACUUGGCUCAGAUACCAUGCCCUAGCAGUGCCUGGGGAGUUGUACUGUAGUCAAGGCCAUCAAUGCCUGGUGGGAUGUUGAAUUUUGAGGGAGAACUAGCGCUCCAAGAGUUAAGCCAUGCUGAAGCAGAGUUGGCCAGGCCACCUGCUGGCUGGAGAUGAGGAAGAGCACUCGGUAAAUCCCCAGUGACUGACGCAAGGGCUGCUGUAUCUUGGCCCUGCAGGUAUUAGACCCUGCCUCCAUCACACAGAAUGUAAGAGCUAGACUUGGGAGAAGUCCAGUCUUCUCUUUCAGUGGGGGAAACAGAGGCCCAGAGAGGGCAAGGGACUUUCAGGCAGUGAGAUAAUAGCCAAGUUGGCAUGGGACUUGUGCCCAGGCCAAGUUCUCUCAGAGCUCUCCGAAUGCUGCAGUAGGUUAGCAUGCAGGGCUUGUGCAGGUGGGAUGGCUCAAAGUCAGUCUUCAGCUUUUAUUUCACCCAGCAUGCCUCAUGUUAGGCCUGUGGUACAGUGAUUAGAAAGAGAUUAGACCCCAAUAUUCUUGGCUUAGAGCUAAGUUCCGUGGUCCCAGGACUUGCUUGGGGCCUCACUUUCCUCAAGGCAAGCUGGUACCAACCUGCUGCCUGGGCAGCAGGUGCCAGAGAAGAGCUGGGAUUCCAGCCACAGCUGAGGAUGAGCUGGUUGGGCUGCCUUUUGAAAUGUGUCUGUGUCCACACUUGGAAUUCAGCUGAGGCCACGGGGAGGGGCAUGUUAUAAUAGAGGAAAACAAGGGUUUCUGCUGGGGCCUGUCUUCCCUGAUGUAGGCUUUCUCCUUACCCUAGGCCACAGGACUCUGGAAGCACGCAAGAGGUAUUCUUAGAGUGCAUACAUGAGUAUUGGAGGCCCAGGGCUUUGAACAGUGGGGCUUUGUAUAGUCCAAGCUUGACAUUUGGGGCUGAUGGUAGCAGCAGCUGCUGCUUCUGCAGACUUCCAACUGCCAUUGGUUUCUCUCUUUAUGUCUUUGUUUUCCUGAGUACAGCUUCCGAUCCCCUGAUCUACCCCAGGUCUUUUCCGGGAGCCUCUCUGUACCUUUAGAGGUUCCCUUUCAGGGAACCCAAGCUGCUGCCCCCAUCCUACACGUCCUCCCCCUUCACUCAGAUCCUGGGCCCUCUCCUGAAUCACUGCAUGUCCAACCUUUCUCCAGCACCUCCUGCUGCUGCCUUGUUCUCUUAUCUUCCUCCAAGGCCUAUAGUAGCAUACAGCAUAUCCUCCUUCCCCCACUGCAUCCACUUUUAGAAGGCCAGAGCUGUAAGGAAGCUUAGAAAUCAUCUAGUUUAAUCCCCUCAUUUUCAGGUAUGGAAAUUGAGACCCUGACAGGUGAAGUAAGUUGCUCAAGGCCACCCAGCUAGGAAGGUUUCUCCUCAACCGGCUGGCUCAUGAACACCCUGCCAUCUUCCAGUCCACCAGUGCCAAACAGCCAAUAACAUCUCCAGUAGCAGCCCCAUUGUUUUUCUCAGCCUGAUCUUACCUGCUGCCCCAGGCCCUCUUCCCUCCCCUGGCUGAGUUCUGACUGGUCCCAACCAGUGCUACUGGUUCACAGGUCAGACUGAAAUACAGCAGGCAGGCCUCUGGCACUUCUACCAACAGAGAGGGCCGUGCCUGUGGGUCUCAGUUUUGUCCAGAGUGUAUUCAGGCAGAAGCCAGUCAGCCUGCCAUUGAGAGAGGGGUCUUGCGGGUCAGGAAGGGACAUGCUUCUGGAAACUUCCACAGGAGCCUGACCAGCUCAGACCCUACUUAGCUCAGGGAAUCCCUCACCAACACCCCACUCACCAAGCAUCUGCCUUCCCCUAGCUGCUGCUCUGACCUUUCUGAGCCUCUAAUGCCUCUAAAGCUUCUGGGGCAUCUGUCCCCUCGGCAUCUCACCUGCUUGUCAGAGGAAGAGUGGCCCAGCUGGGCCUGGGUCACGCCUGGGUUGGCCUCUCCUGAGGCCCUCCCCACUGUCCUCAGCCACAGGCAAGGCUACACCGCCCUGUUAAAGCCACUCAGCCUCUCCCUUCUAUCCUUCCAGCAGAUGAUCCCUGGAUAAUUUGUGCAGCAAAUCCUCUUUAAUCUGUAAUCUGGGGUACUGCAUGAAGGGAACCUGCCUCUAACCUGCCCCUUCACAGCUCGGGUGGAGGUGGAGAAUAUCUGACAUUCCCCUUUAGGAGGUGUAGUGAUCAGUAACUUGGGCAUCAGCCGGAUUCACUUUGUGAAAACCUUGUUGAAUCCCUGCGGUAACUAAUGGUUUCUCUCCAACUCAUGCAGCAACUCCCCCUCCCUUCCAAAGGCGUCUCCUUCUGGGGAUGUCAGGUGGGCCGUUCCUUUUUCUUUGGGAACUGGCUCAA